AGGGGCCAGGGAUUCCCAAGGGGUGACUCAGUGCCUGCCAUGAAACAGUGGGUAGGUGGAAGUGUAUCUCUGCUCUCUAGAGCUGGCACCAGGAGUUGAGUCUCAGUGGAGGAUGCAUUGGGAUUCAAUUGGAGGAACAGGCCUGGAAAAGAAUAAUGAGAUUGAAGAGGGUCAGUUUGAGGACUCAGGUUGGGGCAGGUUUGGAUUAAGUUAGGAAAAGGAUCUGGGAGGGACUCUGUUCAGUGUAGGUCAACUGAGCAUUAUGUAGCCCAAAGAUAAAUUUAAACCCUGCUUCAAGCUUACAAUCUAGUGGGGAGGCAGACCCAUACCUAGUUAACUGAUUCAAGGCAUGAUGAGUAAACUUUAAGAUGAUUACAGAAAGAGGGGAGAUUAAGUCCAUUUGAAAGCAUCCAGGGAGCCUCUGAGGAGACAGCAUUUGAACUUGCUCUAAUGAAUGGGUUCACUAGGUGGAGGUGGAUGGAAAGGUUCCAUAGGCGAAUAACACGUCUUGAGCGAGCCUGACAAGUCAGAAAAUGCAGUAUGUUCUGGGAAAGGAGCGUCCUGAGGGAGAAGAAGCACAGGUGUGAGGGAACAUGUGAUGAAGAAAGGACCACAGAAAGUCAAGGUCAGAGAUUGGACUGCAUCCUGUGGGCAGUGGUCCAGGUGACGAUGAAAAAGAGGGAGAACAGAAAACUUUGGAAGGUGUCUGCCACAUUGAUCCUGGAAUGUGUGUUUAUUUGGGGUUAUAUAAAUCUGUUCUGUGGAAGCCACCUGAAGUCAGGAAGAGAUGGAGGGCAUCCUUCAGGAGUGAGAUGAGACCUCAUCAUACUUGACUGUCCAGCAUCAUCUCUGAGCCUCAGCCUUUCCUGCCUUUGACUGAAACAGCAGUAUCUUCUAAGCCCUGGGGGCUUCCCCGGGCCCCAGCCCCGACCUAGAACCCGCCCGCUGCCUGCCACGCUGCCACUGCCGCUUCCUCUAUAAAGGGACCUGAGCGUCCGGGCCCAGGGGCUCCGCACAGCAGGUUCUCCCCAUGACACCACCUGAACGUCUCUUCCUCCCAAGGGUGUGUGGCACCACCCUACACCUCCUCCUUCUGGGGCUGCUGCUGGUUCUGCUGCCUGGGGCCCAGGGGCUCCCUGGUGUUGGCCUCACACCUUCAGCUGCCCAGACUGCCCGUCAGCACCCCAAGAUGCAUCUUGCCCACAGCACCCUCAAACCUGCUGCUCACCUCAUUGGAGACCCCAGCAAGCAGAACUCACUGCUCUGGAGAGCAAACACGGACCGUGCCUUCCUCCAGGAUGGUUUCUCCUUGAGCAACAAUUCUCUCCUGGUCCCCACCAGUGGCAUCUACUUCGUCUACUCCCAGGUGGUCUUCUCUGGGAAAGCCUACUCUCCCAAGGCCACCUCCUCCCCACUCUACCUGGCCCAUGAGGUCCAGCUCUUCUCCUCCCAGUACCCCUUCCAUGUGCCUCUCCUCAGCUCCCAGAAGAUGGUGUAUCCAGGGCUGCAGGAACCCUGGCUGCACUCGAUGUACCACGGGGCUGCGUUCCAGCUCACCCAGGGAGACCAGCUAUCCACCCACACAGAUGGCAUCCCCCACCUAGUCCUCAGCCCUAGUACUGUCUUCUUUGGAGCCUUCGCUCUGUAGAACUUGGAAAAAUCCAGAAAGAAAAAAUAAUUGAUUUCAAGACCUUCUCCCCAUUCUGCCUCCAUUCUGACCAUUUCAGGGGUCGUCACCACCUCUCCUUUGGCCAUUCCAACAGCUCAAGUCUUCCCUGAUCAAGUCACCGGAGCUUUCAAAGAAGGAAUUCUAGGCAUCCCAGGGGACCACACCUCCCUGAACCAUCCCUGAUGUCUGUCUGGCUGAGGAUUUCAAGCCUGCCUAGGAAUUCCCAGCCCAAAGCUGUUGGUCUGUCCCACCAGCUAGGUGGGGCCUAGAUCCACACACAGAGGAAGAGCAGGCACAUGGAGGAGCUUGGGGGAUGACUAGAGGCAGGGAGGGGACUAUUUAUGAAGGCAAAAAAAUUAAAUUAUUUAUUUAUGGAGGAUGGAGAGAGGGGAAUAAUAGAAGAACAUCCAAGGAGAAACAGAGACAGGCCCAAGAGAUGAAGAGUGAGAGGGCAUGCGCACAAGGCUGACCAAGAGAGAAAGAAGUAGGCAUGAGGGAUCACAGGGCCCCAGAAGGCAGGGAAAGGCUCUGAAAGCCAGCUGCCGACCAGAGCCCCACACGGAGGCAUCUGCACCCUCGAUGAAGCCCAAUAAACCUCUUUUCUCUGAAA